GGUGAUCCGCCCGCCUCGGCCUCCCACGGUGCUGGGAUUACAGGCGUGAGCCACCGAGCCCGGCCCACCACCUGCCGUUUUUUAAACCCAUAAGCCAGGCAUGGGUUUUAUAAUUUUAAAUUGUUCAAAAAACCAAAAGAGUAAUAUUUUGUGACAUGAAAAAUUAUAUGAAAUUCAGAUGUUGAUGAAUAAAGUUUUAUUGGCACAGAGCGUGCACAUCUGCUCGCAUGCUGGCUUGUGGCAGGGCUGAGGGGCUGUGACAGCCCCAUAUGGCCCACAAAGCUGAAAGGAUUUGCUGUGAGGCCCUUUACAUAAUGCAUUUGCUGAUGCCAGCUCUAAAUAUCCAUAUUUGCAUUCAGAUUGGUUUCAGAAAUAAAUAUGCGUUGAAUGCAGCUGGGCCUGUGAACGUGGUGGUUGAAUUCAGCUGGGCCUGUGAACUUGGUCGUUGUGUUUAGAAUGUGUUGUCUUUCCCAGGUGUUGUGUGUUUGUGCUGCCGAAGCUGCUGAAGGCGGCCUGUAGAGGGCAGGGGCCCAGGCAGGCACAGUCACUUCACUGGUGUCUUGGUUGGUGCUUGGAGCACCUCAGGAGGGAAUAUGUCCUUAAGGAAGGAAGACAGGCCAGACAGAGGGGCCUCGGAGUGUUGGCUUCUACCAGGCUCCUGCUGAGGUGGGCGCUCAGGGAGACGGCUGGAGGAUCCGAGGAGAGCCAAAGCCCCAGGCGGUGCCCUCCCCUUCUCCUUCUAGAGCAAAGUCCUGGCCCACUGCCUGUUUAAAAGCACUUUUUUCCAACAAUACACACUGUAAAAUUUGAAGAAGUUUUCAGUGAACACCGCCGCUGCCACUCACCUCCGGAGUUUGCCGUGGGCAUUUGCUGUGCUGGUGCCAUCACACCUGGCAUCACCCCGGCCUCCUGGCAUCACCCCAGCCUCCGUGCUUCCUGCCCUGUGCUCACCCGUCCUCCUGCUUGGGGUUUUUAUUGUAAAAUACACAGAACGUAAAAUUGACCAUGACAGCCACCUUAACGUGCACCACUCGGGCACAGUCCAUUCACAGCGUGGUGCCUCCAUCCCUUCUACCUGCUUCCAAACAGUCCAUCCCAAGAAGAAACCGGUACUCAUCAGCAGGCCCUCCCCAGCACCCACCCCCAGCCCCGGCAGCCACUCAGCCGCCUCCUGCCUCUGCGGACCGGCCUGUUCCGGAGGCUUAAUGAGCAAAUCACAGCCUGUGUGGCCCUUGUGUCUGCUUCCUUCCCUCACAUGAAGCUUUCCAGGGCCGUGCGCGGUGUGGGGUGCCCUUCCUUUCGAUGGUUGGGUAGUGUGCCGCGGUACGUGCGUGAGUUUCCUGAGACAUAACACGUUACCACAGGCCAGGUGGCCUUAGCGGAAAUGGAUUCUUGCCGGAUUCUGGAGGCCAGAAGUGCAAAAUCAAGGUGUCAGCCGGGCCCCUCCCCCUCAGGCUCUCCAGGAAGGUCCUUGCUGUCCCCUGGCUGGUGGCUGCGUCACUCCAGUCUCGGCCUCGGCCUUCACCCGGCAUCUCUACUGCAUGUCUGCGUCUCUAAGGGCCCAGUCAUAGGAUUGAGGGCCCACCCUGGCCCAGCGUGACCUCAUCUUAGCUCACUACAUCUGCAGAGACCCUACUUCCAAAUGUGGCCACACCCACGUAGUACACGCCGGCCGCACUUUGUCGUCUGCCGAUGGGCGCUCAGGGUGCUCCUGCCUUUUGGCCACUGAGUCGUGCUGCCCUGGACGCUCGUAUGCAGGCCUGCGUGUGGACGUAAGUUUCAGUCUCUUGGGUGUACAGCUAGGAGUGGAGUUGCAGCGUGGAACUGCAGGGUCACACGAUAACUGGGCUUCUGGGGGACAGUUACCAGUUGACUUUGAAAUCUAGACGUGUACAGACAUACGAGGGCCUGUGUAUUUAUGUUGAAAAUAGAUGCACGUGUUUAGAGGCCAGCUCCUGCGAGCAUGCAGAUGCUGGUGUCAGGCUGGGAGGAGGCAGACGGACACAUUCCCCACCUGAAGACCAAGCAGAAGUGGAGGCGAAAGACAGCGUGGGCUGACCGUGGAGCGGCCCCAUCGUGCACGCACGCAGGCGAUGCUGAGAUGGGAUGGGGUGACCUCGGGGUGUAUGGAGAGCCCUCCAGAGAGACCCCGAAUUUGGACCGGAUGGCUGCAGAAGGGCUGCUUUUCCCAAACUUCUAUUCUGCCAACCCUCUGUGCUCGCCAUCGAGGGCGGCACUGCUCACAGGACGGCUACCCAUCCGCAAUGGCUUCUACACCACCAACGCCCAUGCCAGAAACGCCUACACACCGCAGGAGAUUGUGGGCGGCAUCCCAGACUCGGAGCAGCUCCUGCCGGAGCUUCUGAAGAAGGCCGGCUACGUCAGCAAGAUUGUCGGCAAGUGGCAUCUGGGUCACAGGCCCCAGUUCCACCCCCUGAAGCACGGAUUUGAUGAGUGGUUUGGAUCCCCCAACUGCCACUUUGGACCUUAUGACAACAAGGCCAGGCCCAACAUCCCUGUGUACAGGGACUGGGAGAUGGUUGGCAGAUAUUAUGAAGAAUUUCCUAUUAAUCUGAAGACGGGGGAAGCCAACCUCACCCAGAUCUACCUGCAGGAAGCCCUGGACUUCAUUAAGAGACAGGCACGGCACCACCCCUUUUUCCUCUACUGGGCUGUCGACGCCACGCACGCACCCGUCUAUGCCUCCAAACCCUUCUUGGGCACCAGUCAGCGAGGGCGGUAUGGAGACGCCGUCCGGGAGAUUGAUGACAGCAUUGGGAAGAUACUGGAGCUCCUCCAAGACCUGCACGUCGCGGACAACACCUUCGUCUUCUUCACGUCGGACAACGGCGCUGCCCUCAUUUCCGCCCCCGAACAAGGUGGCAGCAACGGCCCCUUUCUGUGUGGGAAGCAGACCACGUUUGAAGGAGGGAUGAGGGAGCCUGCCCUCGCAUGGUGGCCAGGGCACGUCACUGCAGGCCAGGUGAGCCACCAGCUGGGCAGCAUCAUGGACCUCUUCACCACCAGCCUGGCCCUUGCGGGCCUGACGCCGCCCAGCGACAGGGCCAUUGAUGGCCUCAACCUCCUCCCCACCCUCCUGCAGGGCCGGCUGAUGGACAGGCCUAUCUUCUAUUACCGUGGCGACACGCUGAUGGCGGCCACCCUCGGGCAGCACAAGGCUCACUUCUGGACCUGGACCAACUCCUGGGAGAACUUCAGACAGGGCAUUGAUUUCUGCCCUGGGCAGAACGUUUCAGGGGUCACAACUCACAAUCUGGAAGACCACACGAAGCUGCCCCUGAUCUUCCACCUGGGACGGGACCCAGGGGAGAGGUUCCCCCUCAGCUUUGCCAGCGCCGAGUACCAGGAGGCCCUCAGCAGGAUCACCUCGGUCGUCCAGCAGCACCAGGAGGCCUUGGUCCCCGCGCAGCCCCAGCUCAACGUGUGCAACUGGGCGGUCAUGCCCCAGAGACCUUCGCAUCAGACCUGAUCUCACUCAUAGGCACCCACCCAGAGCAGCACCUCCGUGCAGCCUGACAAGACCAGGCCUUGUUCACCUCCAGUAGAGAAACGGCCUCAUCACGCCAGCAUCGGCCAGAAACACAAGCACAGACGUGCCUCCAAAGUUUCACUGAAGUCUGUGUUCAGGCCACAAAGGAUGCGUCGUCGUCUUGUCCAGCCCUGGGGGCCGCAGCAGUCAGGGCCUCUCAGGAGCAGCUUUUCUGUCCCCUGCUUGGGGGUCCCAUAGGGUGGCAUGUGGACGGCCCAGCCAUCCCGCGUGUGCAGUGGCCGCAAAGGCCUGUUUCCCAGCACAGCUGAUGUGGGUCCCAGCAGGGCAGGUCUUCACAGCUCCUUCAGAUGGGACACGUGCGGCCCUCGCUCUAGUCGGCAAAAACGAGCCACACACAGGUCUGCGGUGUCGCUCCUGGGUGCCCAGAGCCCACCGAGCACAGUGGAGAUGGCCGAGCCCAGCCUCGAGGCCCCUGGGCCGUCGCUCACCUGUUUACACGGGCUGGGCGUGGCUGCCCACAGCCCCUGGAUCUGCCGCGCAGGAUUCGGGAAGAAGGCCCCUCGGCAGCUGCAGACUUCAGCCUGGGCUCCUGCUGUGCGGGCGAAAAGGCCCAGCUGAAGCCUCUUUCCAGGGCCAGACCCGGCUGCAGCGUGGGAGCCGCUGGGUGCCCGCCGUGCCGUGGGAAGGAAGGUGGUGGCUCUGAACAGCCAGGGAGCCACAGCGUGGGCCGGCGGAUGUAACAGGAGAGCACCGGCCAUCGGGAGCACCUACCAGCAGUGAGGACCAUGGAGGGCAGAUGGCCUUGUCCCUGCCCAGGGACAGUCCACCCUGCAGGGUUAUUUAGGACUGGGCAGGGCAGGGCCACCUCCGUUAGUUGGGGGGCGGGGGGCGGGGGUGCCUGGCAAGUUUCAUAGGAAGAUAUUCAGGGCCCUUCCUUCAAAGGGACCUGGGCAGCUGGCGUCCCCGCCUCUGGACUCAGUGGUGGAGCAGGGAGGUCCCUGUCUCAGGACCCCUGAGUCUCGGGGCCCCAGGAGCCCAGGGCCACCAGCCGUGGAGGAGCCCUGGCCUUCUGCCUUCCACACCCAAUCCCACUCCGUGCUGCUGGGUCCUUCUCUACGACCCAGGCUGCAGUGGCUCCACGGGCGCAGGCCACACCUGCCAUGGAGACAGUGGGCACAGGGCAGGGGAGGUGGGCGCACACAGCCUGGCUGCCACUGCCAUCUCCUGGGCACUGGGGGAACUGCCCCCACCGCCACACCUGUGCUCUCUGCAGGGGGAAAAGUGCCAACUCAGACCUGGCGAGCUGAGCCACUGGGGUCUGAGGGGCCCAGAUGCCACCGUGAGCAGAGCCAUGGGGGAGAUGCACAGACACGCGUGUGAAGCCUGGGGGCCCUCCUUACCCCUUCCCUGCCCUCUGUCCCCGCCAACUCCAGGCCAGCCCCAGGAGAGGGGCUCAGUGGCGUCUCUGGCACAGAGGAGAGGGAGUGUGGCCACCUGGACCCCUGCUUCUGGGACAGCUGAGCGGCCUUUGAGAAAUGCAGAUCCCCCAUCCAGACUCAAACACACCCUGCGGCUGCCUCUGCUGCCCCUGGAGUUUGGGAGCAGCUUCCUCACCCAAACCCACUCCUGCUCUGGUGGCCAAGGGGGCAGGGACACUCAUGCGGCAUCCCUGCUGCCGCCUAGGGCUGGAGACUGUCCUUAGUACCCUGAGCAGCACCCAGAAUCCAAAGUCUGUCCCCGGAAAGUGCCCUCAGGGCCAUGCGGCGUCUGACGUGGCACAGAAGUGGCCUGGAUGGGGACACAGAACCAAACUGCACUCAUUUCAGCCAAGAAGGCUCCUCUUAGCGGCAUAAGUCUCCCUUUCUGUUGCCAGGAAAAGUGCCCUCCCAUCAAGCAAGGCUUCCGCUAAGCAAGGCUGCACUGUGAGGUCCACACACACCCAGGCGAUGGAGGGGUGCGGGCUCCGCUCAGCACCGCACUGAACUGAGCCCAGCAGCGCAGUAGGGACUGGCUUCUCCCUGGGAAAGGCUUCUUGAGAGGCUGAAGCUGCAGGAGAGGGUGAUGAGUUGAGAAGCUCAGGGUGGGCCCUCCUGGGAGGACCGCCUGCCCUUUCUAACACUGCUGGCCCUCGGAGGCCCUCAGCCACUUGGCAGCUGCAUCCCCCAUACCCGGGACCUCCCCACCAAGUUCUCAUUUCUCCAAUGGCAGCCUUCAGAGCUGAGAGGCCGAGUCAAGAGGGUGCCAUCUCCCAAGUUCCCAUGAUUCCUGGGGAGCGUCUGUGUAGCUGCCCACCUGGACCGAGGUGGUCCCCACACUGAGGCCAAUUGGUUGGGGUCCGGGGUUGACCUGGGCAGGGGACACAUCAAAACUGCUCGAGGCCAAGCGCGGUGGCUCACGCCUAUAAUCCCAGCACUUUGGGAGGCCAAGGCAGGUGGAUCACCUGAGGUCAGAAGUUUGAGACCAGCCUGGCCAACUUGGGGAACCCUUGUCUCUACCAAAAAUACAAAAAUGGUUGGGCGUGGUGGCUCACACCUGUAAUCCCAGCACCUUGGGAGGCCAAGGCAGGUGGAUCACGAGGUCAGGAGUUCAAGACCAGCCUGGUCAAGAUGGUGAAACUCCGUCUCUACUAAAAAUACAAAAAUUAGCCAGGCGUGGUGGCGCGUGCCUGUAAUCCCAGCAGCUACUCACUCAGGAGGCUGAGGCAGGAGAAUCUCUUGAACCCGGAAGGCAGAGGUUGCAGUGAGCCAAGAUCGCGCCACUGAACUCCAGCCUGGGUGACAGAGUGAGACUGUCUCAGAACAGCAACAACAAAAUGCCCGCUGCUGCUGGGUCCAGAAGAGCUUGAAUAACUGCAUGUUCUUUUUCUCAAUUUUCAUUUCCCAGAACUGGGCACCUCCGGGCUGUGAAAAGUUAGGGAAGUGUCUGACACCUCCAGAAUCCAUUCCCAAGAAGUGCCUCUGGUCCCACUAGCACCUGCGCAGACUCAGGCCAGGCCUAGAAUCUCCGGUUGGCCCUGCAAGUGCCUGGAGGAAGGAUGGCUCUGGCCUCGGUCCUCCCCCAACCCUGCCCAAGCCAGACAGACAGCACCUGCAGACGCAGGGGGACUGCACAAUUCCACCUGCCCAGGACCUGACCCUGGCGUGUGCUUGGCCCUCCUCCUCGCCCACGGCGCCUCAGAUUUCAGGACCCUCCUCCUCGCCCACGGCGCCUCAGACCUCAGGACCCUGCCGUCUCACGCCUUUGUGAACCCCAAAUAUCUGAGACCAGUCUCAGUUUAUUUUGCCAAGGUUAAGGAUGCACCUGUGACAGCCUCAGGAGGUCCUGACAACAGGUGCCUGAGGUGGCUGGGGAUACAGUUUGCCUUUAUACAUCUUAGGGAGACACAAGAUCAGUAUGUGUAUGGCGUACAUUGGUUCAGUCAGCCUUCCACUGAAUACACGAUUGAGUCUGGCCCAGUGAAUCCGCAUUUUUAUGUAAACAGUAAGGGAACGGGGCAAUCAUAUAAGCGUUUGUCUCAGGGGAGCCCCAGAGGGAUGACUUCCAGUUCCGUCUGUCCUUUGUCCACAAGGAAUUUCCCUGGACGCUAAUUAUGAGGGAGGCGUGUAGCUUCUUAUCAUUGUAACUAUGUUAUUUAGAAAUAAAACGGGAGGCAGGUUUGCCUAAUUCCCAGCUUGA